AUGCGCUCCAGGCUUCGGCCUCUUCUUCCGGCCAGUCCCCGGCCUCGGGGUCAACGGCUCAGGGGACCCCCUUCUUCUGACUCCGGGCCCGGACCCCCCUCCUCUCACUCAGGGAAAACCGCGCAGGGACCCAGGACCCUCAACUGGGGCGACCUAGAGGGCCCCAAACAUCAGUCCCCAAGUACCCCCGCUGCUGAGGUCUGCCUGCACAGCUCCCUCCCUGCCUCAGCCAGAAAGCAAAGUGCAAGGACCAGCAGCAACUUGUGUGCCUGGAGCCUUGCAAUGGCUACGAAGAUGGCUGAGAUUCCUUCUAGCCCAUAUGAGCCGGGACAGCGAGGCAUGAAGGAUACUCAGAGAGGUGAUGCCCCUCAAAGAGGAAGCCCAGAGCCCCGAAUCCUGCAGUUGGCCCGAGUGGGAAACGUAUAUCUGAAGGAGGAAAGCUCAAGGAGUGGGCGACUGGAAGCUAAGAAGUGGAUCCCAACAAAGUUCCUUGAGAACCUCUCUGUCCCACACGUUGACCUCGGUGGAAACCAGCUUUGGUCUGGAAUACAGCUAAAAAUGCAGAAAAUGUGGUUAGAACUGCAGGAUCCUGGUCUCACUAAUAGCUGGAAAGAAAACGGUUUAUAUAUCCAGCCGAAAUCUUUCUGCUCAACGAACGCGGGCGCCAGCCGUGAGAGGAGAAGCUCGGGUUUGUGGAAACUGGCAAUGUUGUCCCCUGAAGCCGGCUCGGGCACCAAGCUGGGUGCGGUGGGGGCCGCGCUAGGUCCGGGUGCGCACCGAGCGCUUUGGAGAGGGUCAGGUUCAGCACCGCGAACAGCGGUAGCCUCCGCCUCUCUCCUUCCCUGGCAGACACGGUUCCCUCCUCCUUCUCCUCACCCCCCUCCUUCUCUUCACCCCCCUCUACCCCCUGCUUCCGGGCUUCAGGACCCGGGCCGGCAGCACCGGCUGCGAGGGUUGCCGAAGGCGCACGGAUCUGGGCGCUGA